AUUGCCCCAGCUAAGCAGCGAGAGCUUGCUGAAGCCCAGAGGGCUGUGGGACCAUGAGGGCAGCUCUCUGGACCCUGGGACUCGGGCCCCUUCUUCUGAAUCUCUGGGCAGUCCCCAUUGGUGGACCAGGUGCUCUGAGGCUGGCGUACAGACACAGCACGUGCGACGGAGUGGUGUUGGUCCGACACCACGGGGCAUGGGGAUACGUGUGCAACCAGGAGUGGACGCUGGCAGAGGCCUCUGUCGUGUGCAGGCAGCUGGGCUGCGGCCCUGCCGUGGGCGCCCCCAAGUAUGUCCCGCUGCCUGGAGAGAUGGCCCAGCCCUGGCUUCACAACGUGUCCUGCCGGGGCAACGAGUCCUCCCUCUGGGAGUGCAGCCUUGGCUCAUGGUGCCAGAGCCCGUGCCCCCACGCAUGGGUGGUGGUCGCGCUGUGCUCCAACGGCACUUUCCGGGAGCUCCGGCUGGUGAAGGGCCGCAGUCCCUGCGCGGGACUCCCCGAGAUCAGAAACGUGAAUGGGGUGGACCGCCUCUGUGUCCUGCAUGUGGAGGAGGCCAUGGUGUUCUGCCGGGAGCUGGGGUGCGGCCCUGUGCUCCAGGCCCCCCGCCGGGACGUGGGCGUCGUCAGGAAGUACCUGGCCUGCAGGGGUACCGAGCCCACCAUCCGCAGCUGCAGACUGGACAACAACUUCCGCAGCGGCUGCGACCUGCGGCUGGACGCAGAGGUGGUCUGCUCAGGACACACCGAGGCCCGACUGGUGGGCGGCGAGCACCCCUGCGCCGGGCGCCUGGAGGUGACCUGGGGCACCGUCUGUGAUGCGGCCCUGGACCUGGCCACGGCCCACGUGGUGUGCCGGGAGCUGCAGUGUGGGGCGGUCGUGUCCACGCCCGAGGGCGCCCGCUUCGGCCGGGGCUCGGGGCCGGUGUGGACGGAGGCCUUCCGCUGUGCGGGCAACGAGUCGCUGCUGUUCCACUGCCCACGGGGGCGUGGGAGCCAGUGUGGGCAUGGUCACGACGCGGGGCUCAGGUGCUCAGAGUUCAGGAUGGUCAACGGCAGCAGCAGCUGUGAGGGCCGCGUGGAGUUCCAGGUGCAGGGGUCCUGGGCACCCCUCUGUGCCACCCACUGGGACAUAGCAGAUGCCACCGUCCUCUGCCACCAGCUCAACUGUGGCAACGCGGUGGCCGCACCUGGAGGAGGCCAUUUUGGGGACGGGGACGCUGCCAUCUGGCCUGAUGCCUUUCACUGUGAGGGGACAGAGUCCUACUUGUGGAAUUGCCCAGUAAGCACCCUGGGGGCCCCGGCCUGUGCCCCGGGAAACACAGCCUCCGCGGUCUGCUCAGGUCUGGCCCACGCCCUGCGACUGAGGGAAGGACAGAGCCGCUGUGACGGCCGCGUGGAGGUCUCCCUGGAUGGCGUGUGGGGCCGCGUCCUGGACGAUGCCUGGGACCUGCGCGGCGCGGGCGUGGUGUGCCGGCAACUCGGGUGCAGAGGGGCCCAGCAAGCCUAUGACGCACCUGCCCCCAGCCGCGGAUCCGUCCAGGUGGCGCUGAGCCGCGUGCGCUGUCUGGGCACCGAAACCCGCCUGACUCAGUGCAACGUGUCCGCGACCCUGCAGGAGCCCGCGGGGACCUCGCGGGACGCCGGCGUGGUGUGCUCCGGUGAGGUCGGAACCGCGUCCCCCAUGGCCCGUCGCCACGGGAUCCCGGGCGCCCUGACUCUGUCUCUCCACAGGGAGCCUCAGGGUGCGGCUGGCCGCGGGGCCGGGGCGCUGCACGGGGGCGCGUGGGGCACCGUGUGUGACGAUGCCUGGGACCUGCGGGACGCGCACGUGGUCUGCAGGCAGCUGGGCUGUGGCCGCGCCCUGAGCGCCCUGGGGGCCGCACACUUCGGAGCCGGGGCAGGGCGCAUCUGGCUGGACGAGCUGGGCUGCCAGGGCCACGAGUCUGCGCUGUGGCAGUGCCCGUCGGCGGGCUGGGGGCGGCACGACUGGAGGCACAAGGAGGACGCCGGCGUCUUCUGCUCAGAGUCGGUGGCUCUGAGGCUGCGAGGUGGGACCUGCUGCUGUGCUGGGUGGCUGGACGUGUUCUACAAUGGGACCUGGGGCGCCAUGUGCAGCAAUGCCCUGAAGGACCUCUCCUUGUCCAUCAUCUGCAAGCAGCUGGGGUGUGGGGUGUGGGGAGUGGGGCUGGCUGGAGAACAGGCCCUUCCCCUCUGCGGGCACCGGGACCGCCUGGGUGGACAACAUCGAGUGCCGCAGGCUGCCCAACUCCACUCUGUGGCAAUGCCCUUCCCACCCAUGGCACCCGCACUCUUGCGACCUUCGAGAGCAGGAUUGUCAGAGGACAGGCCACAGGCUGCUGGGGAGCCCCUCAACUGCUCCUCCUGGCUCGGCUGCCCAGAGGAGGGCGCACUGCGCGUGCGCGGGGGCGAGGACCGCUGCUCCGGGCGCGUGGAGCUCUGGCACGCGGGCUCCUGGGGCACCGUGUGCGACGAUGGCUGGGACCUGGCGGACGCGGAGGUCGUGUGCCGCCAGCUGGGCUGUGGUCGGGCCGUCGCCGCCCUGGGGGCCGCCGCCUUUGGCCCUGGCUCCGGGCCCGUGUGGCUGGACGAGGUGGGGUGCCGGGGCAGCGAGGCGUCCCUGUGGGGCUGCCCUGCGGAGCGGUGGGGACGCGGAGACCGCGCGCACGAGGAGGACGCGGGCGUGCGCUGCUGGGAGCCUGGCCCAGGCCCCCCACUGCCUGCAGCUCCCUUCCGGACAUUCUGGGUGGUCAGUGUCGUCCUGGGAUCCCUUCUUGGUCUUCUCCUUCUGGGCCUCAUGGCUUUUCUGAUUCUGCCUCGAGUCACACAAGCCAUGCAGAGGGGUCUGGGAAGAUCCGAGGUAUCUCCUGGAGAAGCCAUCUAUGAUGUCAUUGGGGAAAUGCCGCCAGCAGGACUGUACGAGGAAAUCAUGGAGGCCGAGGCUGUGCUCCAAGAUGAGGAGGACGGAAGUGUGGUGAAGGUGGACACAGAAGCCGCAGUUUCAGGGGAGGUGUCUAACCUCCUGGAGGGACAGUCUAUACGUGCGGAGGGAGGACACAGCAGACCUGUUUCUCAGGGAUAUGACGAGGCUGCGUUUCCUCUGGAGGAGAUGACGUUGUAAAGCAACCUGAGGAUGAGAUACACCAGCUGGCUGUCGAAAUCACAGCUCUUCAUUUUCUUGUACAAUUGUAGUGGAUUUCGUGAGAACACCUUGGAUGCCUUUCUCUUGCAAUGUCCUCCAUGUCCAUGUAAAAUCCAGUCCUUCCAGGCCCUGCCUGGCUCUAAACCUCAUCCCCUUCGAGGGCCAUCUGCUGUGGACAGUUGUGCUGUGUAACCUUCAGAUUUCCCACACAUUACAGCAAAUGCAAAUACACAUAGAAAUCAGUGGUUCCAUUUGUGGUUUAGAGACACAUGGUGCCAUCUUCAUCUUCCGCUCCACAGCUCGCUUCUGGCACCCAGCAGUGGGUUGCAGAGCUCCCCAUGCCAGAACCUUCCUCUUUUUUCUUAAAAACUCUUCUUAAUUGAAUCCAAAGUAUCUUUUAAAUGUUCUACUUGUGUAAUCAUGUCAUCUGUGAAUAUUCAGAUUUAUCUUCUCCUUCCAAUCCGUGUACAUUUAAUCUCUUUUUCUGUGCCUUAUUUCGGGGGCUGGGACCCUUCAGUCCAGUGUUGAAGAGAGGCAGCCAGUGGAGGUCUUGUCUCAUUCAAGGACUCAGAGCAAAUGUGUUCCACAUUUAAUUUCACUAUGAAAUAUAAUAUUUGAUGUUCAGUUUUGUAGAUGCUAUUUAUCAGAUCAAGGAAAGCCCAGUCUAUACCUAAUUUGUUAAGGGUUUUGCUUUUUAUCAUAAGUGUUGACUUUUAUCAAAUUCUUUUUUGUAUCUAUUAAGAUGAUAGAUGAUUGAUUUUCAUAUGUUAAAUUAACCAUGGGUUAAACAAACUUACCUUUAUCAUGAUAUAUUAUUCUUUUUGUAUUUCACAGGAAUUAGUUUGGUAAUAUGUUGGGUCAAUGUUUAAAAAAGAAAAUGAUGUGUAAUUUUUUUCUUUUAUUGUAGUAUUUCUGUUUAAUUUUUGGUAUGAGGAUUAUUCAGGUCUCAUAAGAGUUAGGAGUAUAUUCUCUUUUAAAAAAUAUUUGCUAAUUUACACUCCCACCAACAGUGUAAAAGUGUUCUUAUUUCUCCACAUCCUCUCCAGCAUCUGUUGUUUCCUGACUUUUUAAUAAUCGCCAUUCUAACUGGCAUGAGAUGAUAUCUCAUUGUGGUUUUGAUUUGCAUUUCUCUAAUGACCAGUGAUGAUGAACUUUUUUUCAUAUGUUUGUUGGCUGCAUAAAUGUCUUCUUUUGAGAAGUGUCUGUUCAUAUCCUUCACCCACUUUUUGAUGGGGUUGUUUGCUUUUACCUUGUAAAUUUGUUUAAGUUCCUUGUAGAUUCUGGACAUUAGCCCUUUGUCAGAUGGAUAGAUUGCAAAAAUUUUCUCCCAUCCCGUAGGUUGCCUGUUCACUCUGAUGACCUAUCAAUGAUAGACUGGAUAAAGAAAAUGUGGCACAUAUACACCAUGGAAUAUUAUGCAGCCAGAAAAAAGGAUGAAUUCAUGUCCUUUGCAGGGACGUGGAUGAAGCUGGAAAACAUCAUUCUCAGCAAACUAACACUGGAACAGAAAACCAAACACUGCAUGUUCUCACUCAUAAGUGGGAGUUGAACAAUGAGAACACAUGGACACGGGGAGGGGAACAUCACACACUGGGGCCUGUCAGGGGGUGGGGGGCUAGGGAAGGGAUAGCAUGAGGAGAAACACCUAAGGUAGAUGACGGGUUGAUGGGUGCAGCAAACCACCACGACACGUGUAUACCUAUGUAACAAACCUGCACAUUCUGCACAGGUACCCCAGAACUUAAAGAAUAAUUUAAAAAAAUUUGCAAGA